AGGAGUAGCAGCCACCGCACGAGGCAAGUGAGGAGAGAAGAUGCUGUAGCGUCCUCACCGGCUGCCAGCAGGGAAAUGGUCCAGGAGUGCUGGGUGUGAGCCUCCCUUCUCCUCAAGCCGGAGACUGCGGUUGUCAUUGAUCAAUUGAAGAAGCAAGGACCCGAAAUCACAGACAUUAGCAAUGAUGUGUGAAGUGAUGCCCACGAUUAAUGAGGACACCCCAAUGAGCCAAAGGGGGUCCCAAAGCAGUGGCUCGGACUCAGACUCCCAUUUUGAGCAGCUGAUGGUGAAUAUGCUAGAUGAAAGGGAUCGUCUUCUAGACACCCUUCGGGAGACCCAGGAAAGCCUCUCACUUGCCCAGCAAAGACUUCAGGAUGUCAUCUAUGACCGAGACUCACUCCAGAGACAGCUCAAUUCAGCCCUGCCACAGGAUAUCGAAUCCCUAACAGGAGGGCUGGCUGGUUCUAAGGGGGCUGAUCCACCGGAAUUUGCUGCACUGACAAAAGAAUUAAAUGCCUGCAGGGAACAACUUCUAGAAAAGGAAGAAGAAAUCUCUGAACUUAAAGCUGAAAGAAACAACACAAGACUAUUACUGGAGCAUUUGGAGUGCCUUGUGUCACGACAUGAAAGAUCACUAAGAAUGACGGUGGUAAAACGGCAAGCCCAGUCUCCCUCAGGAGUAUCCAGUGAAGUUGAAGUUCUCAAGGCACUGAAAUCUUUGUUUGAGCACCACAAGGCCUUGGAUGAAAAGGUAAGGGAGCGACUGAGGGUUUCUUUAGAAAGAGUCUCUGCACUGGAAGAAGAACUAGCUGCUGCUAAUCAGGAGAUUGUUGCCUUGCGUGAACAAAAUGUUCAUAUACAAAGAAAAAUGGCAUCAAGCGAGGGAUCCACAGAGUCAGAACAUCUUGAAGGGAUGGAACCUGGACAGAAAGUCCAUGAGAAGCGUUUGUCCAAUGGUUCUAUAGACUCAACCGAUGAAACUAGUCAAAUAGUUGAACUACAAGAAUUGCUUGAAAAGCAAAACUAUGAAAUGGCCCAGAUGAAAGAACGUUUAGCAGCCCUUUCUUCCCGAGUGGGAGAGGUGGAACAGGAAGCAGAGACAGCAAGAAAGGAUCUCAUUAAAACAGAAGAAAUGAACACCAAGUAUCAAAGGGACAUUAGGGAGGCCAUGGCACAAAAGGAAGAUAUGGAAGAAAGAAUUACAACCCUUGAAAAGCGUUACCUCAGUGCUCAGAGAGAAUCUACCUCCAUACAUGACAUGAAUGAUAAACUAGAAAAUGAGUUAGCAAAUAAAGAAGCUAUCCUGCGGCAGAUGGAAGAGAAAAACAGACAGUUACAAGAACGUCUUGAGCUAGCUGAACAAAAGUUGCAGCAGACCAUGAGAAAGGCUGAAACCUUGCCUGAAGUAGAGGCUGAACUGGCUCAGAGAAUUGCAGCCCUAACCAAGGCUGAAGAGAGACAUGGAAAUAUUGAAGAACGUAUGAGACAUUUAGAGGGUCAACUUGAAGAGAAGAAUCAAGAACUUCAAAGAGCUAGGCAAAGAGAGAAAAUGAAUGAGGAGCAUAACAAGAGAUUAUCGGAUACGGUUGAUAGACUUCUGACUGAAUCCAAUGAACGCCUACAACUACACUUAAAGGAAAGAAUGGCUGCUCUAGAAGAAAAGAAUGUUUUAAUUCAAGAAUCAGAAACUUUCAGAAAGAAUCUUGAAGAAUCUUUACAUGAUAAGGAAAGAUUAGCAGAAGAAAUUGAAAAGCUGAGAUCUGAACUUGACCAAUUGAAAAUGAGAACUGGCUCUUUAAUUGAACCCACAAUACCAAGAACUCAUCUAGACACCUCAGCUGAGUUGCGGUACUCAGUGGGAUCCCUAGUGGACAGCCAGUCUGAUUACAGAACAACUAAAGUAAUAAGAAGACCAAGGAGAGGCCGCAUGGGUGUGCGAAGAGAUGAGCCAAAGGUGAAAUCUCUUGGGGAUCACGAGUGGAAUAGAACUCAACAGAUUGGAGUACUAAGCAGCCACCCUUUUGAAAGUGACACUGAAAUGUCUGAUAUUGAUGAUGAUGACAGAGAAACAAUUUUUAGCUCAAUGGAUCUUCUCUCUCCAAGUGGUCAUUCCGAUGCCCAGACGCUAGCCAUGAUGCUUCAGGAACAAUUGGAUGCCAUCAACAAAGAAAUCAGGCUAAUUCAGGAAGAAAAAGAAUCUACAGAGUUGCGUGCUGAAGAAAUUGAAAAUAGAGUGGCUAGUGUGAGCCUCGAAGGCCUGAAUUUGGCAAGGGUCCACCCAGGUACCUCCAUUACUGCCUCUGUUACAGCUUCAUCGCUGGCCAGUUCAUCUCCCCCCAGUGGACACUCAACUCCAAAGCUCACCCCUCGAAGCCCUGCCAGGGAAAUGGAUCGGAUGGGAGUCAUGACACUGCCAAGUGAUCUGAGGAAACAUCGGAGAAAGAUUGCAGUUGUGGAAGAAGAUGGUCGAGAGGACAAAGCAACAAUUAAAUGUGAAACUUCUCCUCCUCCUACCCCUAGAGCCCUCAGAAUGACUCACACUCUCCCUUCUUCCUACCACAAUGAUGCUCGAAGUAGUUUAUCUGUCUCUCUUGAGCCAGAAAGCCUCGGGCUUGGUAGUGCCAACAGCAGCCAAGACUCUCUUCACAAAGCCCCCAAGAAGAAAGGAAUCAAGUCUUCAAUAGGACGUUUGUUUGGUAAAAAAGAAAAAGCUCGACUUGGGCAGCUCCGAGGCUUUAUGGAGACUGAAGCUGCAGCUCAGGAGUCCCUGGGGUUAGGCAAACUCGGAACUCAAGCUGAGAAGGAUCGAAGACUAAAGAAAAAUUUUCAAUCCAGAAUUGACUAGUUUAUAACAGAAGAAGGUUCAUUCAAUUGUAGGAGAUCUGGAAGAUCAAGGUGAGGAAACUGAAAAGUUGAAGGCUCUCAUUUUGAAAUAUAAGACAUAUGUUUGCUGGUCAUUUCUUCUUCUCCUGACUGAAUAUAUGCUGAUGUUGGCAAGGAAAACAUAAUGUCAAUAAUUGGAUCUGAUCUCAUUCAUUAGAUGGUAACAUAACCUAUUUUUUUAUGUUAAUUAAAACUUACUUGCCAAUUACUCACAAUGGUCUUUCACUGAAGAAUAUUUAUUCUUGACAGAAUCUUUCUUACUAUUAACAUAGCCUUGACACUUCUGACAUGGAGAGAAAAAUAAUGAGGCUAUAUGCUACUAUAAAUAAAUAUGUGUAGAAAAGAAUGUAUCAAUAUUUACAAUAAGAAAAAUUAAUCAGAAAAAACUUCUCUGCAAAUAUAUAUUACCUCCUAUAUGAAGUUUAUAAUAUAUUAGCACAAAAUAUGGGUCAUUUAUAACUAUAGAUUUUUGUCUUUUGCAGAACACAUUUGUUUGAAAGUCAUGAGGUGAAAUUCUUAACAUUCUAAAGUGAUAUAGCUGCUUGAAAUAGUUCUUAACUUUAUUUACUAUGGAAGAGAAGAAAGCUCAUAAAAACUAUGAGAAAUCAGAUAAUUUAUACGAAUUGAUAACAAAAAUAUUAGAAAUUUGUGCAAUGCUUUUUGAGCAGUAUCUUUUAAAUUUGUGUUUUCUGUUUAUUUUCAUAUUUUAUCUUAUAUUUUAUAUUUUAAGGUAUUUAUACUGUGUAAGUUUUCUAUUUUAAAAAAUGAUCAAGGAACAUCUAAUAAAUAUUAGGUUUCACUACGUGCAAAUUUAAUCAACUUGUUUUAUAGGGAAGUGAUUCCUAGAUAGCUAGUAGGCUCAGAAAGAUUAUGUUGUCCAUGGUGAUAACUAGUCCCAAAUGCUUUUGGCAAUUUUCCUGGAAAGCUCAGAAAUUGCCUAUUUUUUCAGAGCUCAUCGUAGAGUUCACAGGUAUGUUGACAAGAAAAUCAUUUUAAAAUCUAAAAACUAUCUCCUUUUGGUCUUAAUUUCAUUUCUGUGGGGUGUAUGAUGUGAAAAAUAUGAUAAAUUUCUUGGGACAGUGUAGUGCCAGUGUUUAUGAACAUUUCUGCUUUUGUUUAUGUGAAAAUCUAAGGAGUUUCCCACAGAUGCUGUGGAGUUAAGGCCAAAAAUAUGCAUUUUUUUCAAAGUGCCGAUUUAAUAAAAAGUACACGGUUUCUCUGAAUGAAUGCCUUGAGAGGAGGCAUGUGCAGGGUGUUCCAUUGCACAUCAAUCUUUUCUUUAUAAUAAUUGUGCGAUAAAAAAGAAGAUGCUCUAACUUGCCUAAUUUCUGACAUAGGAAUUUCUGCUUUCUAUUUUGUUAUAUUGAACAUGUUUUAUGAGUUGUAGUAACAAUUUUAUUUUUUAAUAAUUAGGCUAUUAUGCUUGUAAUAUAUUUUUAAAACAAUACUCUCAUGAAUUUUUGUUGAAUUAUUUAACUUCCAUAUUUUCUCAAUGCCUCUACUACAUCCAGGGAGCAAGUGGGUUCUUCAAAAGCUAUAUGUGUAUCAAUGUCGUUUUAGUGAUGAUUUCUGGUAAUAUUGGUGAACCAAUAUAAUUUAUGGAUGUUUCCCCAAAAACAACAUUUAUAAACACCUAUUCAAAUAAUUAAAUAUUUCUACCACUGAAAGAGCCACAAUAGACACAAACUUGAUGUUUAUUUUGCCAGUCAAAUAGAGAAGGAAGUAAUAUGGCCACCGAAGAAGAGGAAUAGAACAUUUUUACACUUUCUUAUGUUCUGAUUACUAGCCAUAUAUGUUUACCAAAAUAGUAAUUAUUAUUACAGCAUUGGUUGGAAUAAUAACAUUAUGGAUCUGGAAUGGACUUUACACAUUUCUAUUGCCAGGGAUUGUGUUGAGGAAAUUGAAGAUCAGAAUCUGCUAAUAAUUUUGACCAAACUGUGUAUGAGAAAUAGAAUCUAGAUUUUCAGAUCCUCAAACUAGGAAGGACAUUCUUCACUUCAAGUUGCUGCCCAUUCUAAUGUCUGCUGUUCUUUUUUCUUGGGCCUUAGCAGUAGGCUUAUAAAGCUAUAUAAAAAUCUAAGUGCCAAUUAAUAAGUUAUUGUUUCUACUGGUAAAAUAGCAUGGAAGUGGCCUGAGGUAAAGAAUGUCCUUUACCAAGAUUUCUUGAUUUCCUCCUGGGAUGUACUCGAGGCUGGGAAAAUGUGGUCAUGCAUGUUUCAGAGUGGCUCAUACUCAAGACAUAGACUUAUUGGUCAACUAUUAGAACUACCCUCAGCCUGACUAUGCUUUUCGACGCAGUGAGUAUGUGUGUCAUGAUGAAAUACAAAAUGGCACCAUGUCUUUCUCAUACCUGAGCUUUCUCACAUCUUAAAUAAUGCUCUUGUUUUAUUCCAUGGUUUUCUUUGGAUUGAACUGUAUCCAUUAACAUUUGUGUGCUUUUCUUUUCCAUCCGUCCUUCUCCAUCUCAUGAAAAGCACAUCUGGGUAAGUUGAAUCACAAUGGCUGCUGAACAUGUUUAUUUUCAGCGCCAUCUUUUUUUUUCUUUUUUCAGAGUAUUACUCUUUUGAGUUGUAACACAAGCUGCACUGCCUCUGACCUGAAAUGAAAAUCAUGAAGCAUAUUUAUUUCCACACAGUAAAAGGAAUCAUUGGUUCAGAGAAAUGUUCACAUUUUAAUUAAUUAUGUAAGCUUUUGGGCACUUGUAUUUCUUCAGUUUUAUUAUACACAUGUCAAAAGACAUUCUAGACUCCUUCCCUCUAGUUUUCAAGUAAUUCCCUAAAGGGUCAAUGUGGCAAGCAGCCAGGCUCAAGUCAUACUUUGAGACCACUCAGGUACUAUUGAUUGUGCUGCCUGUCUGAAUUGCCUCCACCUUUCUUUCUUUCUUUCUUUCUUUUUUUUUUUUUUUUUUUUGAGACAGAGUCUUGCUAUGUUGCCCAGGCUGGAGUGCAGUGGCGCGAUCUCGGCUCACUGCAAGCUCCGCCUCCCAGGUUCAUGCCAUUCUCCUGCCUCAGCCUCCCGAGUAGCUGGGACUACAGGCACCCACCACCACGCCUGGCUAAUUUUUUGUAUUUUUGGUAGAGACGGGGUUUCACCGUGUUAGUCAGGAUGGUCUCGAUCUCCUGACCUCAUGAUCCACCCGCCUCGGCCUCCCAAAGUGCUGGGACUACAGGCGUGAGCCACCACGCCGGGCCGCCUCUACCUUUCUUAAUGUUCCACCUGUGUUAUGUUCAAGAGACAAACUUAUUCAUCAAUGAAUAGAACGGCACAUAUCUGAAAAGGGUUAAAUGCUGUUCUUCCCUGGAGAGCUUUUACAUAUAGAGAGCCAAGAAUAAUCCUUGGUUUUGGUUGAAUGUGUGUUGUUCCCAUUGUUUCCUGUACUACUGGUUGAUUUCUAAAGCUUUAAAAACCUGAAUUACUCAGAUAAUGGCUUCAAAUUUUAAAUCCUUUUCUUUGAGCUAAAAUUAGAGUAUUUAUCUAUUCCUAACAGAAAUUUGACUUCAAAGUAAAAAAGUAAAAUAAAAUAUGCAUAAUAUUUACAUUGGUGUAGACUACUGCAUUUGUAACAUGGUGAGCUCAUUAAAACACUUUGGACUGAGAAGAAGGUAUUGCUUUUAAAUUUAAAGCAGUGUUAUUUUUUAUCAAUAAAAUGACUGCAAUGAGAUACAAUUAUCCAGGAAACUAUUAAACAUAUUACUAGUUGGCUAUAUAAAUAUUUUGUAUGCCAGUACAAAUUCUUGUACUUUGUAAUAUUACUUUAUUAACUAGUAAGGUUUAUAUUAUUUUUAAUAUAAUUUUAAGUUACAGUUGCCAUUGCCAAAAUGACUUGGUGAUGUAUUAUUUGCUUCAGUUAGGAUGUUUUACAAUAUUGAGGAAUUAAGAAAAGCUCUAGUAAGGUGUUCUUAAAAAUGCAAGGCAGGUUUUGUUUAGAGUACUCGUCAACCAUGUUGGCCAAAUGAAUAUUGUAAGCUCUUUUUGAAAAUAACAAAUAUUAUAGACAUUGAGUUUUAAAACACAGUUUUCAUGUCAUCAUAUAAAUUGUCUUCUGUUUUCUAAUGAUUUUUAAUUUUUCAGAGGAAAAUAAUUUCAAGAAAUAAAACUUAAUUCCCCUGAGUCCUUAUUGAAUUAAAUAUUGAAAAACAAUGAAUGAAUGAUGCAUUCUUAUUAAUGGACUGUAAGAAACUGAUAUAAUGGACUUCAUUCUACAAUUCGGUUUCUUAUUGUCUUACACAUGCUCCUCGAACUUAAACAUUUUAGGACCUUAACACCAUUUCCCUAGUACAAUUACUAAAAGAAAGCUUUGGAUAAUAUAAUAUCAGGGAAGAUAGUACAACAUAGUGAAGAUGACAUAGGAAGAUGUGAGGAGCAAACAACACUGAAUUAGGAAUCAGAAGAUAGAGUUUAAAUUCCAUCUUCCCCACUUACUUGCUACAUGGCCCUGAGUGACUGACAUAUUCUUUGUACUUACUAAUAUUAUUAUCUACUUGUCUGUACCUUCAGAAGCAUACAAACUAUACACUUCCAAACUGGGUAAAAGAGGGCUUAAAAUUAGAUGAAACACUAGAGCAAUCUAAUCUAAGUGGUAUUCAUAUAACCUGAAAAAUUACAAUAUUCUCCAGUAGGUCCCCAAUUACUAUUAGGAAGUGACUGGAAAGUACAGACUAUGGUGUCUUGCAAAAGUGAAAUUGUUUAAUGGGGAGGAAUAUAAGCCCCUCUCAUUUUCAAUAACAGCAUAAAUAAUUGUAUGAUUCAAUCAUAUUUGUGUGUAUGUGUGUGUGUGUCAGGGGGGUAUUUAUACCUUUUUAAUGGCUUUGAAAAUAUUUAAAUUCAAAAUACAGUAAGGAAGGAGAUUACAUAACUCGCAACUCAAUUCCCAAAUACAUUUCUUUCCUGAGACUAUGCCCUAUAUUUCAGAGAAGCUUGAAGAUAAACGGUUUAAAUAUGAAUGAAUUUUAGUUCCAAUGUAAUGAAAUUAUUUGAAAUCUAAACAGCCUAGCAUGUUUUACUGGAAUCUGAAUAAAACACUACUUAAAUAUGUCAUGGAUUUUCAUACAUUUUCACCAAAUGUGAAAAUAUGCAAUAAUAGGAUACACAGGCACACACGCUUGCACUUGCACAUACACAAAAUCACAGUAUGCUUUGCUUUCAAAUCAAGUCAAAUUUAAUGUUGAAUUUGAAACUCUUAAUUUUAUGAAGCUAAAUAUGUAUAGUUAGGUAAUCAAUCUUCUGAAGCAACUGAUUGGAAUUUGUAACAUAUUUCUGUUUAGAAUAAUUAUGUUAACUAAGAUAUACAUGUUCAGCUUGCAGAUGUUAAAAAAAAUAAUUGAGUUGGCACCAUACUUUGCAUUUGCUGACCAGAAUUUCAACUAGCUUCUCAAAUAUGUAGUUUUAGUUUUUACAGACUUAAUCAAGUAUGGAUUCCUGAAUAAUAAGUCCAUUCUUUGGUUGAAAUUUGAGGAGGUUACAUCCUAUUUACCCUCUUGAAAGCUGAAUUUUAGUGAAACAAUAUACAUUUUACAAUUAAUAAUAGUGUGAAGUCUGUGUACAUUUCCUGCUACUAUUAUGUAAGGAAGAUUUAUUUUCUGUGAUGCAAAAUUAAGUAUAUUGCAUUGUCACAUUAUUUGACUUAUAUUUUAUUCUUCAUUCUUAUCAAGCCACAUAUGUAUUUCUUCUGGUUUUAUCAGUAAGUACUUCUUAUGUGCCAUAGUAAAUCAGUAGCUCUGAAGGUAAAUUUUUCACCCAGAGAAUUAUUUUGUAUGGUUAUUACAAAAUCAAUUGAAAUGAAAUGAAUGGCAACAAAUUCAACUUUUCUAUCUCAUUCAUUUAAACUAGGCUAACUUUUCUCUGGCCAAGAUGUACAACCUGAUAUUACUAGGGAAUAACAAGAAAAGAAAAGCCACAGUUCGUUUGUUCUUUUAUAAUGCUGAGGAUUGAAAUGUGUGACAAUAAGAAGGUAAAGACCUUAUGUAUUAACCAGGAAGUCAAAUAAAUGUAUGCCACUUCUAAAAACAAAUGAACCAUAGGAAAAGAAAGAAAAGUAGGGGACCAUUAUUUUAUUUUACACUUACAAUAAGGAAGGUGCUAUUAUCCUCAUUUUUCAGUUAUGAAAAAUUUCAGAAAUGUUAAUUGGCUAAGAGAUGGCAUGGAGGUUAAGAGAGCUGACUCUGUGGACAGGUUAUUGGGGUUCAAAUUCUGAUUCUGCACCUCGACGGUUCCAUGACUCCAACUGGCCUCUGUUCUUCGGUGUUCUCAUCUGCAAAUGUGUGUCAAUAUGUAUCUUAUUGGAUUAUUAUGAAAAUUAAAUGAAUUAAUACACAUAAAAACACUUAGGAUAGUGCUUCAUAGGUAGUAAGUGAUAAAUGCACAUUAGUUACUGUUUUGUGUGAUCCAAAGCCUAAUUUGUCUGCAUCCAGAACCUUUGCUCUUUCAAACCACUAUAUUUCAUCUUAUAAGAAUAUGAACUGGUUCAGAUGAACAGGAGAGCGCAUUAGAUGUAUCUCAAUUAUAGCACUUACUGUAUUAAAUUGUAAUGCAAUUUAUUUAAUUAUAUUUAGAUUACAUUUUAAAUUUUAAGUGAAAGUAUAAUAAGUACAAGUAUAAUAGAUACAAGUUAUGGUAUUUGCAUAGAAGAGAGAGUUAAUUCUGCCUGGGAGAGGACUUAGAAUCUUAAUAGAAAAAAAUAAAGCAUGAGUUCUGUCUGAAGGAUAAGUUAAAGUUGUUAUGAUGGUGAUGUGAAGAAGGAUGCUCUUGGCAGAAGAAAAGGGCAUAUAGCAAGACAUGGAGGGGUAAAAUCGAAUGAGGUAUUUGGGUAAUAGCAAAUAUUUGUGUUAGUUGAGCAGAAAAAGCCAGGGAGACAGCCAGAUUGUGAAGCGUCUUUGUGUAAGAUAUUUGGCCUUUAUUUUGAGGACAGUCAGGGAGGCUUUUAAACAGGUGAGUCUUACAAAAAGAUUUGUGUUUAGGAAGGUCUCAGUGGAGGUUGGAAGGGACAAGUUACCAAAUGAGAGAUAGAGAGAUUCUAGGAGCCCAUCACCAUCAUCAUCAAUUGAUGAGGGCUUAAACAAAAGCUUUGGCAGUAUUCAGUUAGUCUAGAAAAUGUCUUUCUGAAUGUUAGAUAUAACAUUGUAAUCUUUUCUGCAGCCAACCUGGGUAACUGUGAUGCAGAAUUCUUAUUUCUUUUUGAGAUGCAAUGAACAGUUGGAAGUUAUAAAAAUAUAGAAUACUUUAAAAAUGCCCUAUAAUCAAGGAUCCUAGGUGAUUGUCAACAUUGUGAGUUUUUUGGAUUACAAUUUAGCAGUCAUUCAAAAGAUGUUCUUGACUAGAACAUCCAGAGAAAGAUGCAUGAUACGGUUGAAGAACAAACUCUUAUUUCCAGGAUUUUACUGUCUUGGGUUGGAGAUGAGGCUGCGGGCACAUGGUGGUAACCAGUGAUCUCUAUGAGUGAGAUUGACACUACAGGCUUCCAGAUUUUAAAGGAGAAGAGGAUAAUUGUAGAUUGGGCUGAUCACAAAAUAUUUCAUAUAAAAGGGAAGCCAGGAGUUAAGUAAACACAAGGUUGUUGAUAGUUGAAAAAGUAGCGAUCAACUUACCAGCUCUGGGAAGUGGUAUUUGCAAAGGUGGAAUUGGUAAUGCACAAACUGUGAAAGUACUUUUCAAUUCUGGUUAGAAGGAAAGGUAAUUAGAUAAUUAAAUCAAGAUUAAACCAGGAAUCUCUUUGUAAUGAAGAUUAAAAAUAAUCUUUUAGACAUUUGAGGAAAGACUGAAGGGGCUUUAGAGGACAGUGCUAUGAUUAUUUAAAGUAAAACCUGGCCAGGCACAGUGGCUCAUGUCAGUAAUGCCAGCACUUUGGGAAGCUGACGUGAGCAGAUCACUUGAGGCCAGGAGUUCGAGACCACCCUGGCUAACAUGGUGAAACCCCAUCUCUACUAAAAAUACAAAAAUUUAGCCAGGCAUGGUGGCACGUGCCUAUAAUCACAGCUACUCAGGAGGCUGAAGCAGGACAAUCACUUGAACCUGGAAGGCAGAGGUUGCAGUGAGCCGAGAUCAGGCCCCUGCACUGCAGCCUGGAAGACAGAGUAAAACUCUGCCAAAAAAAAAAAAAAAAAAACAACGAAACAAACAAACAAACAAACAAAAAACAGUAAGAAAGAAGCUCACAUUUAUUGACCAUUGCCUUUUGUGUGAGUUACUUUUGUAAUCAUAUUACACAUAUUUUCUUACAAAACCUUUGUAAAAACCCUAUUAGAUGGGUUAUCAGCUUCAUGUUCCACAUGAGGAAACUGAAUCACAGCAAAAUACAGUGACUUGUUAUGGAUGUGCAGCCCAAAAGGACAGGCAAAGGAAUCAAGCUCAAGCAAUUUGAUUUUGGGAGCCACUUUCUCACCCACUCUGCCAUAAAGUUUAUCUUCCAGGCAGAUUUUUUUUUUCUUUAAUGUCAGUGUAAGAAGCCUGGAGAGAAGGACCAAUUAAAGGCUGAGAAAAAAACUGUGGUAGCAGUGACAAUAGAAAGUAAAGGAAGAUACAUUAGAAAGUAUGAAGGGGAAAAUGACAGGCAUCAAAUAGAAGGUGAAUGAAAUGGCCAUCAUGAGUGACAGAGGGGACAGUGCUGUAUGGUAUUUGGACAGUCAUACCACAAAUUGGCAUCCCAGAAUAGCAUGCUAAAGUGAGAGGUCUGUGAAUAAAGUCUCUUUUCACUGACAGAGAUAAACCAUCCACAGUAGGAAGAAUGAGGAGGAGACAUACUGUUCCCUAUGGUCUGUGACUUUUUUGAGUAACUAAUGAAUUUCAUUUUUCAGAAUUGCAAAUAUAAACACUAACAAAUUCAAGUUUUACCAUUCCAAUAUAGUUGCCAAUAGGAUAGCUAUUUAUGGAAAGGAUUGUCUAAUAAGUAAUUUUAAAUAGUUGAGACAUGGCUCAUGCCUGCAGGAGAUUAUAGUGUAGCGGAAAUAAGGCUGUGUACAUACGGUGAACGGCCUACCAGAGUCUUGCACAUGAUAUGAGUGGCAUCACUCAAGGGAUAGAGAAAAUUUGAAUGGUAUGAAUUGAGGAAAGGCCAUUCCAAAUGGAGAGAAAGUCAGUAGAACAGAAGAGGUAAAGUGCAAAGAAUGGUGAGUAUCCAUUGUAGCUAGAGAGAAUAGAUACAGUAGGUAAAUCUGGAAAUGCAAUUUAGGGGCAGAUCAAGAAUGACCUUAAAGGCCAUUCUUCCAAUAGUAAAUUAAAAGCCAUUAUAGAAAUUGGAGUUAUAUAGUAAGCUAAUAAAUAUGUUUACUGAGUUAUAUAGUAAGCUAAUAAAUGUUUACUUUAAGGAGGUUAAUCUGAUGGUAGCACACACAAUGAAUUGCUUUGGGAAAAUAAGAAAAAAUUGGAGAACGGAAAUUAGUUAUCUAUUGAAUACAUAUUGGCUGCUAGGUGCUUUUGUAAGUAUUAUCUUAUUUAGUUCUUAUAAAUUGAGAUCAAUUUAUAAUCAUCUUCAAAUAUGGGAAAAUUAAGUCUCAAAGAGAUUAAGUACAUAGCCAAAAAACACAUAGCUGGUAAGAAGUUAAUUUGCCAUGCAUUCAUUCAUUCAGUUAUGAUUUAUUGAAUGUAUGCUGUGUGCCUGAAUCCCUAUUCCAAUAACCUCUCACCAUUUCUGCUGCCACAGCUCAGGACAAAGCAACCAUUAUCUUCUGCUUGAAAAUUGAAACAACCUUCUAACUUGUAUCCUUAGAUCACAACUCUGGCCUGACUCAAGUCCGUGCUAUCCUCAACAGCCAGAAAUGCCUUUAUAAUGUACAAAUUAUUUUAUGUUCUUGUGCUUAAACCCUCUGAUGGCUUCUUACUAUGUUUAGAAUAAACUCCUCUUCAGCUCCCAAA